AACAGGCAGAUUUGCCUGCUGAGGGUGGAGACCCACGAGCCGAGGCCUCCUGCAGUGUUCUGCACAGCAAACCGCACGCUAUGGCUGACAGCCGGGAUCCCGCCAGCGACCAGAUGCAGCACUGGAAGGAGCAGCGGGCCGCGCAGAAAGCUGAUGUCCUGACCACUGGAGCUGGUAACCCAGUAGGAGACAAACUUAAUGUUAUUACAGUAGGGCCCCGUGGGCCCCUUCUUGUUCAGGAUGUGGUUUUCACUGAUGAAAUGGCUCAUUUUGACCGAGAGAGAAUUCCUGAGAGAGUUGUGCAUGCUAAAGGAGCAGGGGCCUUUGGCUACUUUGAGGUCACACAUGACAUUACCAAAUACUCCAAGGCAAAGGUAUUUGAGCAUAUUGGAAAGAAGACUCCCAUCGCAGUUCGGUUCUCCACUGUUGCUGGAGAAUCGGGUUCAGCUGACACAGUUCGGGACCCUCGUGGGUUUGCAGUGAAAUUUUACACAGAAGAUGGUAACUGGGAUCUCGUUGGAAAUAACACCCCCAUUUUCUUCAUCAGGGAUCCCAUAUUGUUUCCAUCUUUUAUCCACAGCCAAAAGAGAAAUCCUCAGACACAUCUGAAGGAUCCGGACAUGGUCUGGGACUUCUGGAGCCUACGUCCUGAGUCUCUGCAUCAGGUUUCUUUCUUGUUCAGUGAUCGGGGGAUUCCAGAUGGACAUCGCCACAUGAAUGGAUAUGGAUCACAUACUUUCAAGCUGGUUAAUGCAAAUGGGGAGGCAGUUUAUUGCAAAUUCCAUUAUAAGACUGACCAGGGCAUCAAAAACCUUUCUGUUGAAGAUGCGGCGAGACUUUCCCAGGAAGAUCCUGACUAUGGCAUCCGGGAUCUUUUUAACGCCAUUGCCACAGGAAAGUACCCCUCCUGGACUUUUUACAUCCAGGUCAUGACAUUUAAUCAGGCAGAAACUUUUCCAUUUAAUCCAUUCGAUCUCACCAAGGUUUGGCCUCACAAGGACUACCCUCUCAUCCCAGUUGGUAAACUGGUCUUAAACCGGAAUCCAGUUAAUUACUUUGCUGAGGUUGAACAGAUAGCCUUCGACCCAAGCAACAUGCCACCUGGCAUUGAGGCCAGUCCUGACAAAAUGCUUCAGGGCCGCCUUUUUGCCUAUCCUGACACUCACCGCCAUCGCCUGGGACCCAAUUAUCUUCAUAUACCUGUGAACUGUCCCUACCGUGCUCGAGUGGCCAACUACCAGCGUGACGGCCCGAUGUGCAUGCAGGACAAUCAGGGUGGUGCUCCAAAUUACUACCCCAACAGCUUUGGUGCUCCGGAACAACAGCCUUCUGCCCUGGAGCACAGCAUCCAAUAUUCUGGAGAAGUGCGGAGAUUCAACACUGCCAAUGAUGAUAACGUUACUCAGGUGCGGGCAUUCUAUGUGAACGUGCUGAAUGAGGAACAGAGGAAACGUCUGUGUGAGAACAUUGCCGGCCACCUGAAGGAUGCACAAAUUUUCAUCCAGAAGAAAGCGGUCAAGAACUUCACUGAGGUCCACCCUGACUACGGGAGCCACAUCCAGGCUCUUCUGGACAAGUACAAUGCUGAGAAGCCUAAGAAUGCGAUUCACACCUUUGUGCAGUCCGGAUCUCACUUGGCGGCAAGGGAGAAGGCAAAUCUGUGAGGCCGGGGCCCUGCACCUGUGCAGCGAAGCUUAGCGUUCAUCCGUGUAACCCGCUCAUCACUGGAUGAAGAUUCUCCUGUGCUAGAUGUGCAAAUGCAAGCUAGUGGCUUCAAAAUAGAGAAUCCCACUUUCUAUAGCAGAUUGUGUAACAAUUUUAAUGCUAUUUCCCCAGGGGAAAAUGAAGGUUAGGAUUUAACAGUCAUUUAAAAAAAAAAUUUGUUUUGACGGAUGAUUGGAUUAUUCAUUUAAAAUGAUUAGAAGGCAAGUUUCUAGCUAGAAAUAUGAUUUUAUUUGACAAAAUUUGUUGAAAUUAUGUAUGUUUACAUAUCACCUCAUGGCCUAUUAUAUUAAAAUAUGGCUAUAAAUAUAUAAAAAGAAAAGAUAAAGAUGAUCUACUCAGAAAUUUUUAUUUUUCUAAGGUUCUCAUAGGAAAAGUACAUUUAAUACAGCAGUGUCAUCAGAAGAUAACUUGAGCACCGUCAUGGCUUAAUGUUUAUUCCUGAUAAUAAUUGAUCAAAUUCAUUUUUUUCACUGGAGUUACAUUAAUGUUAAUUCAGCACUGAUUUCACAACAGAUCAAUUUGUAAUUGCUUACAUUUUUACAAUAAAUAAUCUGUACGUAAGAACA